AGUUUCCCGGCGCGGCUGUGGCUCCGCCCUCCGGGCGCGAGGCCCGGGUGGGCCAGAGAGGCAGGUCCUCGUCCCUCGGGCCCGUGGCGCUGUCGUGGAUGUAGGGGUUCCGCUUGCCUGGGCCCUGGGCUAUGCAGAGGGAGACACGAACCAGGGGCUGGAGCUCUGUUUUCAGGCCACCUGACCAGCUGAGGAGAUCGUCAGAAAGGCUGGGACACCAACGGAUGACGCACAAAUGGAGGAAUUUUCAGGCACGGUCAAAGCUAAUGGGAGGGAAAAUACUGAAGUGUAAUAUUCCAGAGUUCUCUCUUGUCUGCUCUGACUCCUGCCAGCUGCCCUGCACCUAGAGGGACAGGAGGCUCUUCUCCGGGGCAUUGCAUGGCCGGGAGCCAAAUGAGCUGGCACCAGAACCUGGUGAGUUGCCUGGCUUUUCAGACCUCAGCCUCCUCACCUGUGAAGUGGGUUGAACAGCUCUUCUCUGCAGAGGAGCUGUUGAGGGCGGUAUGGAACACUGCCAGGCACACAGUUGGCCCUUGACAAAACCAUUGCUGUGUCCCCAGCCUGUUUCUCCCCAAGUCCCAUUGAUGGUUCUCUCUAUCCCUGUUUCCUCAGAAGGUCAGGUUUUCUAAGCCCGAAGGCUUGGAGCCAGGCAGGAGCUGUCUCCCUCUCCAGUGCUGCCGACUCAACCCUUUUCCCUUAGAAGCAGGGAGGGAGGCUCCCCUUGGCUCCCUCCCUCUGCAGCCCUGGCUCUGCGCCCUGGGAAUGCUGCCUGGGGCAGGGCCACGUAGAGAGCAGGGCCAGUGCAGGCCUUUGGGUGUUCCCAGUGGCCAAAGUCCUUUAGUCUGCUUUCCUUUGGGCCCCCUUGCACCCCUGAAUGGAUGACCUGGGGGAUUCCAAGUCGGUUUGGGAGGGGUGACAGCACAAGGCUGGAGGUUGGGAGAGUCUGGCUGUCAUCCCAGCUUGGAUUGUAGUCUGCCAUGUGACCUUUGGGCCAAAGAUAAAUCCUCCCUGGGCCACAGUGUCCCUGCUGGUCAGAUGAAAGAAUCAGAUGAGAUCAUUUCUGAGGAUCUUUCCAGGCUUCAUAUUCUUCUGUUUGAUUAUCCCCCCAAAUAAAUUGGAAAUUGGAGGCCCAAGGAUGAGCCCUGGUUGAGGACGCAGAGCCCAGGGGCCGUCCCAUCCUCCACACUUGGCCCAGCUGUGAGUGGGGGAAUGGGAUUUAGCACCUGAAGCCCCAGAUUUAAAUAUAUCCCCACUCCCCGCCGGGGUCCCCGCACUCCUGCACCUCCCUCCUCCCAGGACGGCCCUGACCUGCAGGCAUUGUUCCCCGCCCAUGCCCAAGCCCCGAGGGAAUUCCAUCGGGUUGGAGAGUCUUCCCUUCUGUAGGGGGCUUUGCUCCUCUCUACCAGUUAUGUGACCUUGGGCAAGUCACUUCAGCUGCCUGACCCCAGCUCCCUAGGACUAGUUGAAGUAAUGGAUAUAAACACCCUUUGGGGACCAAAAGCCCCUAGAGAGAUGAGACCUGGCCCAGGCAGUAAGUCUUCAACAAAUGUAGAAUAGGAGGAUGCUGUAAACAAGCCAGCCAAAACCCACCAAAUCCCUUGGUGGAGGAUAAGGGACAUUUGAGACAGUCUUUAUACAGGAGUCUCGGGCCCCAGGAAGCCAGGGCAGAGAGUCUUUGCCAAACUUCCCCCUGCCUAACAAGAAGGAAACUGAGGCAGGACCCUGCCAGACCCAGAGGCAAACAGGCUGCCCUCCUGUGAACUUGUUGGGGGUCAUUUCCACAAGGGAAUAGUUCUAGAAGACCAGGGUGAGUCAGUAACAAUGGCAGAAUUCCAGUCAGAGGAAGAAGACUUUGGUGUAGCUGGGGCUGGAGCAUAGAGGAGCGACUUGGCUGCCGCCCUGGCCCUGUGUCAGAGGUGUUAGAACCAGAGCCACUCCAUCUUGAGUAGGAGCUGGGUAAAAUAGGGCUGAGACCUGCUGGGCUGCAUUCCCAGGAGGUUAGGCAUUUUUAGUCACAGGAUGAGAUGGGAGUCGGCAGGACUGGUAUCAUAAGAUACAGGUCAUAAAUACCCUGCUGAUAAACAGGAUGCGCUAAACAAGCCGGCCAAAACACACCAAAUCCAAGAUGGUGAUGAAAGUGAUCUCUGGUCAUCCUCACUGCUCAUUAUACACUAAUUAUAAUGCAUUAGCAUGCUAAAAGACACUCCCACCAGCACCAUGACAAUUUACAAAUGCCAUGGCAAUGUCCAGAAAUUACCUUAUACGGUCUAAAAGCGGGAGGAACUCUCAGUUCUGGGGAAAUCUCCCCUUUCUUGGAAAACUGAUUAAUAAUCCACCCUUUGUUUAGCAUAUAAUCAAGAAAUAACCAUAAAAACAGCCAACCAGCAGCGCUCAGGGGUGGUCUGUCUAUGGAGUAGCCAUUCUUUUGUUUCUUUACUUCUCUGUAAACUUGCUUUGACUUCACUCUGUGGACUCACCUCAAAUUCUUUCUUGUGCGAGUCCAGGAACCCUCUCUUUGGGUCUGGAUUGGGACCCCUUUCCAGUACCAUUUUUUCUAGUGAACCACGAAGGGACGAUACCAGAAAACACCCUCAACCCAAAGGAAAUAGACUACAGCCCCAAUUGGCUGACUUUGGAGUCAAGAAACCCCCCCUUCUUGAGCUAUUUACAGCUUUUAACAAUUGAGUAAAGUACGCUCCGGCCUUUGAAUCAAGCAAGACCCCACUGGAUCACCAAAGAGUUAAGCAAAGGAAAUCCCUGCCUCCCUUUAUCUCCGCAGAACCCAGAGGCUGAAAGGGAGGGAGCAGGGAGGAGGGGAAGUGGGAAGCGGCUCUGCCCUCUCCCUCCGCCCUCCCUCCGCCCUCUCUCCCUCCAUCCCCUCCUCUCUCCCUCCUCUGCUGGGCCUGGGGGUCUGGGCCAGCAACAAGUUAGUAUUGCAGACAUGGGCCAAGGAGCCAGAGGCCAUGCAGUGGCUCAGGGUCCGUGAGUCGCCUGGGGAGGCCACAGGACACAGGGUCACCAUGGGGACAGCCGCCCUGGGUCCCGUCUGGGCAGCGCUCCUGCUCUUUCUCCUGAUGUGUGAGAUCCCUAUGGUGGAGCUCACCUUUGACAGAGCUGUGGCCAGCGGCUGCCAACGGUGCUGUGACUCUGAGGACCCCCUGGAUCCUGCCCAUGUAUCCUCAGCCUCUUCCUCCGGCCGCCCCCACGCCCUGCCUGAGAUCAGACCCUACAUUAAUAUCACCAUCCUGAAGGGUGACAAAGGGGACCCAGGCCCAAUGGGCCUGCCAGGGUACAUGGGCAGGGAGGGUCCCCAAGGGGAGCCUGGCCCUCAGGGCAGCAAGGGUGACAAGGGGGAGAUGGGCAGCCCCGGCGCCCCGUGCCAGAAGCGCUUCUUCGCCUUCUCAGUGGGCCGCAAGACGGCCCUGCACAGCGGCGAGGACUUCCAGACGCUGCUCUUCGAAAGGGUCUUUGUGAACCUUGAUGGGUGCUUUGACAUGGCGACCGGCCAGUUUGCUGCUCCCCUGCGUGGCAUCUACUUCUUCAGCCUCAAUGUGCACAGCUGGAAUUACAAGGAGACGUACGUGCACAUUAUGCAUAACCAGAAAGAGGCUGUCAUCCUGUACGCGCAGCCCAGCGAGCGCAGCAUCAUGCAGAGCCAGAGUGUGAUGCUGGACCUGGCCUACGGGGACCGCGUCUGGGUGCGGCUCUUCAAGCGCCAGCGCGAGAACGCCAUCUACAGCAACGACUUCGACACCUACAUCACCUUCAGCGGCCACCUCAUCAAGGCCGAGGACGACUGAGGGCCUCUGGGCCACCCUCCCGGCUGGAGAGCUCAGGUGCUGGUCCCGUCCCCUGCAGGGCUCAGUUUGCACUGCUGUGAAGCAGGAAGGCCAGGGAGGUCCCCGGGGACCUGGCAUUCUGGGGAGACCCUGCUUCUAUCUUGGCUGCCAUCAUCCCUCCCAGCCUAUUUCUGCUCCUCUCUUCUCUCUUGGACCUAUUUUAAGAAGCUUGCUAACCUAAAUAUUCUAGAACUUUCCCAGCCUCGUAGCCCAGCACUUCUCAAACUUGGAAAUGCAUGCGAAUCACCCGGGGUUCGUGUUAAAUGCAGAUUCUGACUCAGCAGGUCUGAGUGGGUCCAGGAUUCUGUGUUUCUCAUAUGUUCCUGGGUGAUGCUGAUGGGGUCAGUCUAUGAACCACACUGGAGCAACCAGGUUCUAGGACUUUCUCAAUAUUCUAGUACUUUCUGAACAUUCUGGAAUCCUCCCCACAUUCUAGAAUUCUCCCAACAUUUUUUUUUCUUGAGACAGAGUCUUGCUCUGUUGCCCAGGCUAGAGUGCAGUGGUGCAAUCUCAGUUCACUGCAACCUCUGCCUCCCGGGUUCAAGCGAUUCUUCUGCCUCAGCCUCCCUAGUGGCUGGGAUUACAGGCGCCUGCUACCAUGCCUGGCUAAUUUUUGUAUUUUUAGUAGAGAUGGGGUUUCACCAUAUUGGCCAGGCUGGUCUUGAACUCCUGACUUCAGGUGACCCACCCGCCUCGGCCUCUCAAAAUGCUGGGAUUACAGGUGUGAGCCACCGUGCCUGGCCAAUUCCAACAUUCUUAAAUUCUCUCAUCCCUCCAGGGCUCCCCGUGCUAUGUUCUCUUUACCCCUUCCCCCUCUUCUCUUGCUCAGGCCUGCACCACUGCAGCCACCGUUCAUUUAUUCAUUCAUUAAACACUGAGCACUCACUCUGUGCUGGGUCCCGGGAAGGGUGAGGGGGUCAGACACAGGCCCUGCCCCUGCCCUCAGUGACUGGCCAGUCCAGCCCAGGCGGGGAGAGAUGUGUACAUAGGUUUUAAAGCAGACCCAGAGCUCAUGGGGGCCUGUGUUCUGGGUGUUCAGGUGCUGCUGGUCCUCCAUUACCCACUGCUCCCCAAGGCUGGUGGGACGGGGUCCCGGUGGCAGGGGCAGGUAUCUCCUUCCCGUUCCUCAUCCACCUGCCCAGUGCUCAUCGUUACAGCAAACCCCAGGGGGCCUUGGCCAGGUCAAGGGUUCUGUGAGGAGAGGACCCAGGAGUGUGGGGGCAUUUGGGGGGUGAAGUGGCCCCCGAAGAAUGGAACCCACACCCAUAGCUCUCCCCACAGCUGAUACGGCAUCCUGCGAGAAGACCUGCCCUCCUCACUGGGAUCCCCUUCCUGCCUCCUCCCAGGGCUCUGCCAGGGCCUUGCUCAGUCCCUUCCACCAAAGUCAUCUGAACUUCCGUUUCCCCAGGGCCUCCAGCUGCCCUCAGACACUGAUGUCUGUCCCCAGGUGCUCUCUGCCCCUCAUGCCCCUCUCACCGGCCCAGUGCCCCGACUCUCCAGGCUUUAUCAAGGUGCUAAGGCCCGGGUGGGCAGCUCCUCGUCUCAGAGCCCUCCUCCGGCCUGGUGCUGCCUUUACAAACACCUGCAGGAGAAGGGCCACGGAAGCCCCAGGCUUUAGAGCCCUCAGCAGGUCUGGGGAGCUAGAGCAAAGGAGGGACCUCAGGCCUUCCGUUUCUUCUUCCAGGGUGGGGUGGCCUGGUGUUCCCCUAGCCUUCCAAACCCAGGUGGCCUGCCCUUCUCCCCAGAGGGAGGCGGCCUCCGCCCAUUGGUGCUCAUGCAGACUCUGGGGCUGAGGUGCCCCGGGGGGUGAUCUCUGGUGCUCACAGCCGAGGAGCCGUGGCUCCAUGGCCAGAUGACGGAAACAGGGUCUGACCAAGUGCCAGGAAGACCUGUGCUAUAAACCACCCUGCCUGAUCCUGCCCCUGCCUGACCCCGCCACGCCCUGCCGUCCAGCAUGAUUAAAGAAUGCUGUCUCCUCUUGGC